ACUUCUGCUGCUCCCACCUCCUGGGCAUGGUUGGGCAGUUGGAGCGGCUGAGCCUAAGCAUCCUGCACCCGGCCUACGCGCCCAUCGAGCACGUCAAGCAGCAGCUGCAGGAUGCUCUGCCCCCCGACGCCCACGUCCUGGCCUCCCAGCGGCUGGGCAUUUCGCUGACCCGCUGGCCUGACGGACGCAACUUCUUGGUCACUGACUUCGCCACCUGCGAUGAGCUCAUCCAGGUGUGGGGCGGGGGGUGCCCAGGGCUUGGCUGGUGGGCGGGCUCCAUCUAGUCCAGAGUGACAUCCAGGUACUUCCCCGUCAGACGUUUCUGCAGGGGCGGAAGGAGGGAGGGCGGGUGGACCUGUUUGUAGGUGAGGAAACUGAGGCCCAGAGAGGGUCGGCAGGGUGGGUCUGGAGACUUUCCAGGUUGCUGCACACAGAAGGGUCUGGCUGGGGCCCGGCAGAGUCAGGCUGCUGAGUCAGGGCCCCCACAGGGACUGCUCUUUCCAGAGGGCAGCUGGCUAGCCCCAGCCUCCACCCCACUCCAUCCUCCCGCCGCUUUUUGGCGGUGGGUUGACAUUUAUUGAACACCUAUUAUGUGCCAGUCACUAUUCUAGGCACUGUGACUGUAACAGGGAGCAAAACAGACAGAAACCCUUGCCUUCCUGGGGCUUCUAUGCUCAGUGGUUCUGGGGGGCAGGCGGUAUCGAUAAUGAACUCAUCUCCAAGUAAGGAGGUAAGGAACCAUCCAGUAUUGAAAUGAAAUAGGAUGUCUAAAAAAGAUGCUUCACAUACACCCUGACACUAUUAUUUGCCAAUAGUGUGUACGCGCACGCUCAAGUGCAGGCACACAGUGUGACAACCAAAAAUGUCUCUGACAUUGUUAGGUGUCCUGUAGGGGAGAAAAUCACUCCUAGUUGAGAACCACCAACCCAGAGCUUGCAAACUUUUGAAUAUAGGACUUUGUCUCAUGGAACCCUUGGAAACGUCCCAACUCUCUCUGGGAGGUGCAGAACCCAUCCUGGCCCUGACCAGAUGGAGAUGCAGGUGACAGUUUUGUUCCCACAGACUGAUAACAGUCACGGCAGCUAAUGUGUACUGAGCACCUACUAUGUGCCAGGCCCCAUCCCAACUGCUACACAGGCAAGGAGUCUGGGCCACUCUUUGGGGUCCCCGGCUGGCUUCCUCAGGAGCCUGCACCUGGCCUCCUUCCCUGCACACCCACAGAAAGAGGAGGUGGGUGUCAAGACAGAGGUGCUCCAAUCCCUGCUUCCCUUGGAGAGCUUGGCUGGGAGGUGAUGCCUCAGCUCCCUCAUCUGGACGUGGGACUGAUGACACCUCCUUUGCAGGCUGUUGGGAUUAGAAACCGUGCCUAGGAAGGUUCUGAAUGCAAGAAGCAUGCACAGUUGUGUUCCUGCUGACUCUUCUCUUCCUAGGCCUUGGUCUGCACCUUAUACUUUCCUUUCUACUGCGGGCUGAUCCCCCCCGAGUUCAGAGGGGAGACUGCCCCUCCACCAUCACGGUGUCGCCCUUCCAUGGGACAGUGGACAUCUGCCCCCAGAGCACCUCCCCCAACCUGCAUGAGCUGAACGUCUUCAACUUCAGCUUCCAAAUCUCCACUGAGAACUUCUUCCUGGGGCUCAUAUGUCUCAUACCCCCCAGCCUCGAGGUAGUGGCCGACAACUGCAGACAAGGCUACCUGGAUGCCCUGAGGUUCCUGGAGAGACGUGGACUCACCAAGGAACCAGUGCUAUGGACGCUGGUGUCUAAGGAACCCCCAGCCCCGGCUGACGGAAACUGGGAUGCUGGCUGUGACCAACGCUGGAAGGGGGGCCUGUCUCUCAACUGGAAAGUGCCCCAUGUGCAAGUCAAGGAUGUACCCAACUUUGAGCAGCUCUCACCAGAGCUGGAGGCUGCACUGAAGAAAGCAUGUACGAGGGAUCCCAGCCGGUGGGCCCGCUUCUGGCACUCGGGGCCUGGACAGGUGCUGACGUACCUGCUGCUACCCUGCACACUGCCCUUCGAGUACAUCUACUUCCGCAGCAGAAGGUUGGUGGUGUGGCUGCCCGAUGUGCCGGCGGACUUGUGGUGGAUGCAGGGCCUGCUGAGGAACAUGGCCCUCGAGGUUUUCUCCAGGACCAAGGCCCAGCUCCUUGGGCCCAUCAGCCCUCCGGCCACUCGCGUCCUGGAAACAAGCCCCCUCCAACCCCAGAUAGCUCCUCAUAGAGAGGAGCUCGGGCCCACCCACCAGGCCUGAGGGGGCCGAGCAGGGCCAGCCCAGUGACUGGUGUCCCUUGAUUCCUGCUCUGGCCUUUGUCCUGUGUGCCCACAUCUGCCCCAGCGGGAAGAGGCCCUGCCAAUCUCCGUGGAGACCCUGCAGCUUGGAGCCCGUUCCUUGGGGCGCAGCCUGUCAGCAUGUCCCCGGUCACUGUGUACCCAGGUCACCUGCCCUCCCUCUUGCCCCGUCUCAUCAGGGAGAGAAAGGAGGACAGCCACAGAGACACAUGUCUUACUUUCAGAAUUUCCACGGGGGGACUAGGAGGGCAGCAUUGCUGGGGAGAGGGGCUCCUGUUCUGCCGUGGAGCUGCCCACGGAGCACCUCACAGAAGAUUGAGAAAGUGCCUGAUGCCCGCGUCAGAGACCAGAGGAGCCAACUGAGAUGAUGGGGUGGGGGUGCUCCCCCCAGACUUUCUCAGUCCUGCAGCGGCCCUUGGGGGUGACCCCCGGCAUCUACCCCACUCAGGAAACCUUGACUUCUGAAUUCCUAUCAGGUCCAGAGGGUGGAAGGCCCUGGCAGGAAGCAGGAGGAGGAGGAGAGGGGGGUCCAGGUCUUUUCAGGAUCCCAGCUGUGGGUGCUUCUGUUGGGCCCAGUGGCCCCUGCUAUCCCCACAGCCUCAUUCCUGCAGAAGGUUUGUGACGUAGCUGUGCCUGUACCUGGGGCAGAGAGGAUGCCAGGGACACCAGGCCUCUGGCCUCUCCACGAGUCACUGCUCUCCCCAUUGGCAGCACGGGACCCAUGCUGUGCCCCCGGCCAGGCCCUGAGGAAAUGCUCAGCCUCAGUGGAGAUGGGGAGGUUAGAGAGAUGGAGGCGUGAGUGAGAACGGGAAGCAAAGGAAUACACGUGGGAACUAAAGAGAAAAAUGACCAGCCUGGGCAGCAUAGCAAGACCCUGUCUCUAAAAAAAAUAAUAAAAACUUAGCUGGGCAUGGUGGUGCAUGCCUGUGGUCCUGGCUACUUGGGAGGCUGAGGAUGGAGGAUCAUUUGAGCCCAGGAGGUCGAGGCUGCAGUGAACCGUGAUCACGCCACUGCACCCCAGCCCAGGCAACAAAGUGAGCCCCUGUCUCUAAAUAAAUAAAGAGACAAUAAGCCACUCA